AUUCUCUUAUUUGAUGUUAAAGAAAUUAGAUGGUAAAUUAACAUUCCUAUACUUGGAAUAUUCGUCAGUUUUAUUUCAUAUUUCUACUUUCUUUCAAAACUUUUAUUAUGGAAAAUCCAGUACAUAUAGAAAAGUUGAAAAGGCUAAGAAACCCCGUGUACUCAGCAUCAGCAAUUACUAAUAUUUGGCUAACCUUUUUGUAUUUUUACCCCACUCAUAUACCCCCUCAUUAUUUGUUUUUGUUUGUUUUGAGAUGGAGUCUUGAUGCCACGCCCAGGCUGCAGUAGAGUGCAGUGAUCUCAGCUCACUGCAACCUCCGCUUCCCAGGUUCAAGCGAUUCUCCUGCCUCGGCCCUGAGUAGGUGGGACUACAGGCCUGCGUCACCAUGCCCAGCUAAUUUUUGUAUUUUUAGUGGAGACAGGGUUUCACCAUGUUGGCCAGGCAGGUCUGGAACUCCUGACCUCAAGCGAUCUGCCCACCUCGGCCUCCGAAAGUGUUGAGAUUACAGGUGUGAGCCACCUCGCCCAGCUACCACCUCAUUAUUUGGAAGCAAAAUGAAAAUUUAUGUUUCAUCUAUAAAUAUUUCAGCAUGUAUAUAAAAGAAUUUGGUUUGCGUUUCUUUUUUUUUUUUUGAGACGGAGUUUUGCUCUUUUUGUCCAGACUGGAGUGCAGUGGCCUGAUCUCAGCUCACUGCAACCUCCACCUCCCGGGUUUAAGUGAUUUUUCCUGCCUCAGGCCUCCCGUGGAGCUGAGAUUACAGGUGCCACCAUGCCCGGUUAAUUUUUUGUGUUUUUAGUAGAGACAGAGUUUCAUCAUGUUGGCCAGGUUGGUCUUGAACUCCUGACCUCAGGUGAUCCACCCACCUCAGCCUCCUAAAGUGCAGGGAUUAUAGGCAUGAGCCACUGCACCUGGCCUGGUUUGCUUUUUAAAAAAAAAAUUUUUUUUUUUUUUUUUGAGCUGGAGUCUCACUCUGUCGCCAAGGCUGGAGUGCAGUGGCGCAAUCUUGACUCACUGCAACCUCCGCCUCCUGGGUUCAAGUGAUUCUUCUGCCUCAGCCUACUGAGCAGCUGGGACUAUGGGCGCGCCAUCACACCCAGCUGAUUUUUGUAUUCUUAGUAGAGACGGGGUGUCACCAUAUUGACCAGUCUGGUCUCGAACUCUUGACCUCAUGAUCCACUUGCCUCCGCCUCCCAAGGUGCUGGGAUUACAUACGUGAGCCAUCACACCUGGCCGAGUUUGGUGUUCUUAAAUUUAUUCAUUUCCCUCAUUAACUUUUUUUUUUUUUUUUUGAGACAAGGUCUGGCUCUGUCACCCAGGUUGGAGUGCAGUGGUGCGAUUGCGGCUCACUGCAAUCUUUGCUUCCCAGACUCAAUCCAGCCGCCCACCUCAGCCUCCUGUGUUGCUUAGACUAUAGGCAUGCCCCACCAUGCCCAGCUAAUUUUUGUAUGUUUUGUAGAGACGGGAUUUUGCCAUGUUGCCCAGGCUGGUCGCAAACUGCUGGACUCAAGUGAUCCAGUCAGCAUUUUUUUUUUUUUUUUAGUAAAAAAAUAGAAACAGGGUCUUGCUAUGUUGCCCAGGCUAGUCCUGAACUCCUGGGCUCAAACCAUCCUCCUACCUCCGUCUCCCCAAGUGCUAGGAUUACAGGCAUGACCCACCAUGCCCGGCCAGCAUAACGUUGUUUAACAGUGUAUUUGAAUCAAGAUGCAAAUAGUGAUCCCAUCACGUGUACCUAGCUAACAGUCUUCAUUCCUCUCUUCUUUGCCACUCUCCUCAAGCCCCUUAUUUCCUUUUCCCUUUUCUCAUUUCAACUGAAGACCUUUGUACCAGUUCUGGAGCUGUUAAUCACUGACAGUUGGGAACUGCUACUUUUUGUCCUAUUUAAACUUAAUGCAUCUGUACACAGCCAUAUUUCUUCCCCUCUUUCUUAGAGCAGAGUGUCUUCCCUCUUGUCCAAGAUUAACUCAACCACCUGGGUGCUGUGUGUACCACAUAUGUUCUGCCUUUUUAGGGACUGUGCCGUCAGAUCCAUCCACGUUCGCCUCUUUCCCUUAUCCCUCGUUUUUUUUUGUUUUUUUUUUUUGUUUUGAGAUGGCGUUUCACUGUUGUCGCCCAGGCUGGAGAGCAACAGUGCAAUUUUUGCUCACUGCAACCUCCGCCUCUGGGUUCAAGCGAUUCUCCUGCCUCAGCCUCCUGAGUAGCUGGGAUUACAGGCGCCCACCACCACACCCAGCUAAUUUUUGUAUUUUUUUGGUAGAGAUGGGGUUUCACCAUGUUGGCCAGGCUGGCCUUGAACUCCUGACCUCAGGUGAUCCACCCGCCUUGGCCUCCCAAAGUGCUGGGAUUACAGGCGUGAGCCACCGCGCCUGGCCCUUAUCCCUCUUUCUGCUAAUAUAGACGUGCUCACGAUUCUAAUCUUUAAAAAGGACAUUCCCCCUAACCGCCAAAAAAAAAAACCCAUGUAAUUGCAUGUCUCUGUUUGCUACCAUUCCCACAGUCCUUCCCUUCAGUCUAGCUUUUAAGAAAAGUAGUCUGUUCUUGUACUCUCUCCCUUCUCUUGAUCUGUUCACCCUUCCACGCACUUGGAUUCUGGUGGUGGUGGGUUUUAUUCUCCGUCCUGACUGUGCCACUGAAGCAGUGCCCACUGAGGCCACCCUGACCUCUCAUAUGUAAUGGGCAGUGCAGCUUUUGUCUUAUGAGUCCUCUGUUACCUUUCACGUGGCUGCUUUUCUUGUUGAAGCUACCGGAUUCUCUGAGAGAAAUCUCUUCUGAUUGUCCUCUUGCCAAUUCUUUCUUAGUGUUACUGUGGUAUCUUUUCCUCUGACUACUCUUUAAAUGUGCAUUUCCCUCAGGGGUCUCAUUCUUGGUCAUGUUCUUGUGACCCUUUGUCACCCUUUGUUGGGGGCAGUAUCUCUUGUGCCCACCGUGAUCUCUCUCCUGAUCUCCAGACAUGUAUGUUUGUUUGCCUCCUGGCAUUUGCACCUCUUUAUUCCAUAUGUACCACCAGGUAAGAAUGCUCCACUGGGAGCUCAUCAUUCUCAUCAGUCCUGUUCCUUGGCAUGAGCGCUACCACUAGCCUUCUAGUUGCCUAAGUUAGUGGCCCGAGAGUCAUCCUGUCUUCUUUCCUCUCCUUGCUUAGCUAAUCAGUUGCCGAGUCCUGAUGAUGCUGUUUUUUAAUUAUCUCUUUAAUCUGCCUUUUCGUCUUCACCUCCUUCCCUGCUCUGGUCAGUCUGGUCAGUCUUCUCAGAUACACACUGUUGUAACCAUCUCCUUACUGGUCUCCCUUCUCCAACCUUAUCCUCUUUCUAAUUAUCUUCCACUCUUCUGCCCAGAUGAUCUUUUUUAGAUGCUCUCAAAGUCUUCAGUGUCUCCUCAUCUUCAGUAGGAUAAAAUCUAAGCACUUUCGUGUAACACUGAAGGUCUCUCCUGACCUGGUUCCCACCUUACUGUACUGUCUCGUUUCCUUUCACACCUGCUAGGUACUUUAUAUACUGUAGUGAGCAAAACACUAGACAUGGACCCUGUCCUCAGGGGAGGAGUAAUAGCAGUCAGCUUUUAUUGGACUAUGUGCCAGACACUGAUUUCCUCCUCUGAGAAGCCUUUCUCGUUUAUGUUUGCAUACCAUGUAUUAUAGCUGUUACCAUUUUAUUGUGAACUUGGUCUGUCUCUUCACUGCACUGUUGGAGGCCUUUGAUUGUUUCUUUAUCUUUGUAUCCUCAGAGCCUAGAACUGAGUAGGAACCCGGUAAGUAUUUGCUGAUGAGUGAGUCAUUUUUAUGAUUCUUAUUAGCUCUUCUCUUCCCUCACUCCUUAAUAUCCUUUAGUUCUCCUUUCAGAUUGAUGCUCAGACCUUGCUUAUCCAUAUCCAGCAAUACUUUAUAUUGUAUUUACCGUUUCACAAUUUACUUUUGGGAAAGCGCUCUAGCGAGUGCUGAUUUAGAAGAAGAAAUUCACCAGAAACAAGGGCAGAAAAGGAAAAAUUCUCAACCUGGUGUUAAAGUAGCAGAUAGAAAAAUACUUGAUGACACAGAAGACACAGUUGUCAGUCAAAGAAAGAAAAUUCAAAUCAACCAAGAAGAAGAGAGAUUAAAGAAUGAGAGAACUGUGUUUGUUGGGAAUUUGCCUGUUACAUGUAAUAAGAAGAAGCUGAAGUCGUUUUUUAAAGAGUAUGGACAAAUAGAAUCUGUACGAUUUCGUUCUCUGAUUCCAGCAGAGGGAACGCUAUCCAAAAAGUUGGCAGCAAUAAAACGUAAAAUUCAUCCUGAUCAGAAAAAUAUUAAUGCCUAUGUUGUGUUUAAGGAGGAGAGUGCUGCCACGCAAGCAUUGAAAAGAAAUGGGGCCCAGAUUGCAGAUGGAUUUCGUAUUAGAGUUGAUCUCGCAUCUGAGACCUCAUCUAGAGACAAGAGAUCGGUUUUUGUGGGGAAUCUCCCUUAUAAAGUUGAAGAAUCUGCCAUUGAGAAGCACUUUCUGGACUGUGGAAGUAUCAUGGCCGUGAGGAUUGUGAGAGACAAAAUGACAGGCAUCGGCAAAGGGUUUGGCUAUGUGCUCUUUGAGAAUACAGAUUCUGUUCAUCUUGCUCUGAAAUUAAAUAAUUCUGAACUCAUGGGGAGAAAACUCAGAGUCAUGCGUUCUGUUAAUAAAGAAAAAUUUAAACAACAAAAUUCAAAUCCACGAUUGAAGAAUGUCAGUAAACCUAAGCAGGGACUUAAUUUUACUUCCAAAACUGCAGAAGGACAUCCUAAAAGCUUAUUUAUUGGAGAAAAAGCUGUUCUCCUUAAAACGAAGAAGAAAGGACAGAAGAAAAGUGGACGCCCUAAGAAACAGAGAAAACAGAAAUAACAACCAGGAACUGCUUUUUCUUUUCCUGCUGAGUACUGCUAAUAAAAGUGCUAUUAUCUGCUGAUAGCAUCGUCUGCUAUUCAUGUGUUGAGUUUUAUACUUCUUUAUGGAUGGUGUAUGUGAAAUGUGGAGACUUCCACAUUCUCAGUUUAUUCACAUUGUGAUACUACCUUUGAAGGUUUUUUUGUUUUUGUUUUGUUUUUUGAGAUGGAGUUUGGCUGUUGUCUCCCAGGCUGGAGUGCAGUGGCGUGAUCUUGGCUCACUGCAACCUCUGCCUUCUGGGUUCAAGCGCUUCUCCUGCCUCAGCCUCCCAAGUAGCUGGGAUUACAGGCGCCUGCCACCACGCCUGGCUAAUUUUUUGUAUUUUUAGUAGAGACGGGGUUUCACCAUGUUGGCCAGGCUGGUCUCGAACUCCUGACCUCAGGUGAUCCACCUGCCUUGGCCUCUCAAAGUGCUGGGAUUACAGGCGUGAGUCACUGCACCCAAGCCUCCUUUCUCUUUUGCCUAUUAAACCUCUGCUCUUAACCUUA